ACAAAGCGUUGGGUGAGACUCCUCUUGCUCGUCAUGUCUGGCCGCGGCAAAGGCGGGAAGGGUCUUGGCAAAGGCGGCGCUAAGCGCCACCGUAAAGUACUGCGCGACAAUAUCCAGGGCAUCACCAAGCCGGCCAUCCGGCGCCUUGCUCGCCGCGGCGGCGUGAAGCGCAUCUCCGGCCUCAUCUACGAGGAGACUCGCGGGGUGCUGAAGGUGUUCCUGGAGAACGUGAUCCGGGACGCCGUGACCUAUACAGAGCACGCCAAGCGCAAGACGGUCACCGCCAUGGAUGUGGUCUACGCGCUCAAGCGCCAGGGCCGCACCCUCUACGGUUUCGGUGGUUGAGCGUCCCUUUCUAUCAAUAAAAGGCCCUUUUCAGGGCCACCCUA